ACCACGGGAGCGCCGCACCGGCCGGCAUGGAGGAGCGCGGCGAUUCCGAGCCGACCCCCGGCUGCAGCGGCCUGGGUCCGGGCGGUGUUCGCGGCUUUGGCGACGGCGGUGGAGCUCCUUCGUGGGCCCCUGAGGACGCCUGGAUGGGCACUCACCCUAAGUAUCUAGAAAUGAUGGAAUUAGAUAUAGGAGAUGCCACCCAAGUUUAUGUAGCGUUCUUGGUUUACCUGGACCUCAUGGAAAGCAAAAGCUGGCAUGAAGUAAACUGUGUAGGAUUACCAGAACUCCAGCUCAUCUGCCUUGUUGGUACUGAGAUAGAAGGGGAGGGGUUACAGACUGUGGUGCCUACCCCCAUCACUGCUUCCCUCAGCCAUAACAGUUGUACACAGAAGAAAGCCCAUAUGAGGACACAGCAAGAAGGUGGCUGUCUUCAAGCCAAGAAGAGAGGCCUCAUCAGAGAUGGAAUGUUCCUGCACUUCGGUCUGGAUUUCUAGUGUCCAGAACUGUGAGAAAAUAAAUUUCUGUUGUUUAAGCCACCUGGUCUGUGGUAUUUUGUUAUGACAGGCCUAGCAAACUAACGUAAAAUGCUUUGGUACAGCAGCAGGCACAAGGUAGAGAUUCAUUAAUUGUAAUAAUACCAUAUAAAUAAUUAUUGAUAAUGGCACUAUCAAUAAUUGCCAUUGUUAUUGCUUCUAAUAAAACACCCACCCUUCUGGGGGAGAGAGGAAGAAUUUUGGAAACUCCAGUAACAAACAGUCUGCAAAUCCACUUUGAGCUUCUGAUGAGAAAUUGAGGGCACUCGAAAGAAAUAAAUCACAUUCACUGAAAUUUUCUGAUCCUAUUUCUGUACAUAUGUCAUGAUAAUUUGUGUCAAGUAAUAUGACAGCAUCUUUCCUCUGAGGGACUUAAUGUGCUUAUGCCAACUACUUAUCCAUCAGGCAAAUGUUUACAUUCUGAGGAUGAACUAAGGGAAUGUCUUAGAUAGCUGGGAGCCUGAGGCUAGGACUGUGCACUGAGGGGCACUAAUAAAAUCAGAUAAUCAAAUUUCUUCCACCUUCUCUGUGGUUUAGGCUGUGCAGUCUGGAAGCAGGCCAGGUGGUUGGUUUUAGGAAUCACAGGGUUGAGCUUACAGUACAAGACAGAUUUUACUUCAAGUCUAAGUUAGCCUUGACUAAUGAUUGUUCCAUCACUUUUAGAUGUCCAGCUAACUCACUUACAGGCACAUCAGGAAGAGGGACCUCUCAAGACUGUUUUCUCACCAAAACUCUGAGGUUCUGGUUUCAUAACUGUAUUAGUCCAUUUUCACGCUGCUGAUAAAGACAUAGCCAAGACUGGACAAUUUACAAAAGAAAGAGGUUUAAUUGGACUUACCGUUCCACAUGGCUGGGGAAGCCUCACAAUCAUGGUGGAAGGCAAGGAGGAGCAAGUCACAUCUUAUAUGGAUGGCAGCAGGCAAAAAGUGAGAGAGUUUGUGCAGGAAAACUCCCCCUUAUAAUAACCAUCAGCUCUCGUGAGACUAUCAUGAUAACAGCACGAGAAAGACCUGCCCCCAUGAUUCAGUUACCUCCCACUAGGUCCCUCCCACAACACGUGGGAAUUCAAGAUGAGAUUUGGGUGGGGACACAGCCAAACCAUAUUAAUAACAUUCACAUUCUUUCUGGACACCCAAUCAAGCCCUCCACAUGGACCUGUGGGCUGCAGACUCUUGCAGACAGAUCAGGGAGGAGGGCAGAAAAGGCCUCUCAGCAACUGCAGUUCUUUGUGCCUGCAUUUCCAAUUCAGAUGAAUGCAUUAGAAAUGGUCCUAAAAUGUAUUUGAAAAAAACAGAACCAUCUAAGAUCAUUGGUCAGAGCUCCAAAUGGUUUAUAAAGAGGGGGAACAAUAUGCUGACUUCUGAAAAAUGGGAAGGGGGUUACAUUGGCUUGAUUGAAACCAGUUGAAGGAGGUUUUUUGUGUUUUUCCCCCAAGUUUUUCUUGACUAAUGAUUGUUCAGGUCUUUAAAUCAGUGUUGUCCAACUGUCCCCAAAGACUACAUAAGGCACAGUUGAAAUCUGUAUUGUCCCUUGCUGUUACUGCCUCUCCGCUGCCCUUAACUCACAGGAUGAGGUAUUAUAGGUUAUAGAAUCCCUUGCUUUUUAUUCCUUUAUCACAGAUGGAUGAAGUGCUCAAAUCUGA